AGUCUCCCAGUUGCGAGGGCAAGCAAACCCGUCAUGAGCAACUCCCUUCCCCAUCUCUGCUCACCAUGUGGACGCUGAAAUCGUCCCUGGUCCUGCUUCUGUGCCUCACCUGCAGCUAUGCCUUUAUGUUCUCUUCUCUGAGACAGAAAACUAGCGAACCCCAGGGGAAGGUGCAAUACGGAGAGCACUUUCGGAUUCGGCAGAAUCUACCAGAGCACACCCAAGGCUGGCUUGGGAGCAAAUGGCUCUGGCUUCUUUUUGUUGUUGUGCCGUUUGUGAUACUGCAGUGUCAAAGAGACAGUGAGAAGAAUAAGGAGCAGAGUCCUCCUGGCCUUCGAGGCGGCCAACUUCACUCUCCAUUAAAGAAAAAAAGAAAUGCUUCCCCCAACAAAGACUGUGCAUUCAAUACCUUAAUGGAACUCGAGGUGGAGCUUAUGAAAUUUGUGUCCAAAGUGCGGAAUCUUAAACGUGCCAUGGCAACAGGUAGUGGCAGUAACCUCAGGCUUCGAAAGUCAGAGAUGCCUGCAGAUCCAUACCAUGUCACGAUCUGUGAAAUAUGGGGAGAAGAAAGCUCUAGCUGAAUGGAUUUGUGUGUCAGGAGAGAAAAAAAAGAAAAAGUGAAUGGGAGACCAGUAGCCAUAGCAGUGAUGGUUUUGUUUUUGCCUCUCUCACGUCAUCUAGAGCUGUGGGUGGUGAGAAGAACACCGAAAGCUACAUAAUAUGUUUAUUGAUUGGAAUUCUGCUGUAAGAAGAGCUGUUCCUUCGCCGAUGAUUGAUGGAUGGGUUUCUGUAUGGACUUACAGCAUAAAGUUCUGCUCCUCGGGAGUAAAUCUGCGAAUCAGAGCCUUCCUCAGGAAGAUAGCUCUACAGAUGACCCAGGGGAACAAGUACAAGCCGUGCAUUCCAGCACCCAGGAUUUCUUGUUUCAUGUCAUUUUAAAGAACUCAUGGUUUCAGAAAACUAGCGAACCCCAGGGGAAGGUGCCGUGUGGAGAGCACUUUCGGAUUCGGCAGAACCUACCAGAGCACACCCAAGGCUGGCUUGGGAGCAAAUGGCUCUGGCUUUUGUUUGCUGUUGUGCCGUUUGUGAUACUGCAGUGUCAAAGAGACAGUGAGAAGAAUAAG